ACAGCAAGAAGGUGCCAUCUAGGAAGCAGGAAGCAGGGCCUGACCAGACACCAAAUCUGCUGGGGCCUUAGUCUUGAAUUUCCAGCCUCCAUAACUGUGCAAAAUCCAUUUCUGUUGCUUAUAAGCUACCCAGCUUAUGGGAUUUUGUUUAGCAGCCCAAAUGGACUAAGACACUCAAUGUUAGAAGACUUCUUUCUCCUUCCUGCUGGAGAAAUUCAACUGCAUUGCAUGGAGAGCUAAUUAUAUGGAGAGACAACCCCCUGGAGCCUGUCCAUGGAAGGAGAGGCUAAGAACCCUGCUGAGAAAGUGGUCACCAUUACCUCCAUCCUGGGGCCUGACUCCAGUUCCUUACACCCGAAGUUGCUCUACUCACUACUUACGAUGUCAUGCAACAGUUAAGGGUCAGAGGCUCCUAUAGGUCUGCAAGCCAGUUCGCUGGGUGGAGGCGUGUGUUCUAUCAGGCCAGACAAGGUGGCAUAAGUGGAAAUAAACUCAAGCUGAUGCUUCAAAAACGAGAAGCACCUGUUCCAACUAAGACUAAAGUGGCCGUUGAUGAGAAUAAAGCCAAAGAAUUCCUUGGCAGCCUGAAGCGCCAGAAGCGGCAGCUGUGGGACCGGACUCGGCCCGAGGUGCAGCAGUGGUACCAGCAGUUUCUCUACAUGGGCUUUGACGAAGCGAAAUUUGAAGAUGACAUCACCUAUUGGCUUAACAGAGAUCGAAAUGGACAUGAAUACUAUGGCGAUUACUACCAACGUCACUAUGAUGAAGACUCUGCAAUUGGUCCCCGGAGCCCCUACGGCUUUAGGCAUGGAGCCAGCGUCAACUACGAUGACUACUAACCAUGACUUGCCACACGCUGUACAAGAAGCAAAUAGCGAUUCUCUUCAUGUAUCUCCUAAUGCCUUACACUACUUGGUUUCUGAUUUGCUCUAUUUCAGCAGAUCUUUUCUACCUACUUUGUGUGAUCAAAAAAGAAGAGUUAAAACAACACAUGUAAAUGCCUUUUGAUAUUUCAUGGGAAUGCCUCUCAUUUAAAAAUAGAAAUAAAGCAUUUUGUUAAAAAGAAAA